GGUCAGCGCCCGUCCGGCCUGCGGCCCCCCGCCCGCGCCCGGUGCAGCUCGGAGCCUCCCGCCGGGGCUCGCGCCGCCUCCGCCGCCCCCGCGCCCCCCGGCCUCCGCGCAGCGCCUGGGCUGGGGGGGCCACGACCCUCUGCUCUCGGCGGCCUCCGCCUGAGGUACCUGAAGGAGUUCAGGACGGAGCAGUGCCCCCUGUUUUCACAGCACAAGUGCGCGCAGCACCGGCCGUUCACCUGCUUCCACUGGCACUUCCUCAACCAGCGGCGCCGCAGGCCCCUCCGCAGGCGCGACGGCACCUUCAACUACAGCCCCGACGUGUACUGCUCCAAGUACAACGAAGCCACCGGCGUGUGCCCCGACGGCGACGAGUGUCCCUACCUGCACCGGACGACGGGGGACACAGAACGCAAGUACCACCUGCGUUACUACAAAACAGGAACCUGCAUCCACGAGACAGACGCACGUGGCCACUGCGUGAAGAAUGGGCUGCACUGUGCCUUCGCGCACGGCCCCCUGGACCUGCGGCCGCCCGUGUGUGACGUCAGGGAGCUGCAGGCCCAGGAAGCCUUGCAGAACGGCCAGCUGGGCGGCGGGGAAGGGGUCCCGGAUCUGCAGCCUGGGGUCUUGGCCAGCCAGGCCAUGAUUGAGAAGAUCCUGAGCGAGGACCCCCGGUGGCAAGAUGCCAACUUCGUGCUGGGCAGCUACAAGACGGAGCAGUGCCCGAAGCCGCCACGCCUGUGCCGCCAGGGCUAUGCGUGCCCACACUACCACAAUAGCCGGGACAGGCGGCGCAACCCCCGGCGGUUCCAGUACAGGUCCACGCCCUGCCCCAGUGUGAAGCACGGGGAUGAGUGGGGGGAACCCUCACGCUGCGAUGGCGGCGACGGCUGCCAGUAUUGCCACUCCCGCACGGAGCAGCAGUUCCAUCCCGAGAUCUACAAAUCUACAAAAUGCAACGACAUGCGCCAAACCGGGUACUGCCCGCGCGGCCCCUUCUGUGCCUUUGCACACGUUGAGAAGAGCCUGGGGAUGGUGAAUGAAUGGGGCUGUCACGACCUCCACCUCACGAGUCCUUCCUCCACGGGCAGCGGCCAGCCGGGAAAUGCCAAGCGGAGAGACUCGCCGGCCGAGGGUGGCCCUAGGGGCAGCGAGCAAGACAGCAAGCAGAACCACCUGGCCGUGUUUGCAGCGGUCCACCCGCCGGCCCCCAGCGUGAGCUCCAGCGUGGCGUCCAGCCUGGCGUCCAGCGCCGGCUCCGGCAGCUCCUCCCCCACUGCGCUGCCCGCGCCCCCCGCCCGUGCCCUCCCGCUCGGCCCCGCCAGCAGCACUGUGGAGGCCGUCCUCGGUUCUGCGUUAGACCUGCAUCUUAGCAAUGUGAAUAUUGCAUCCCUAGAGAAGGACCUGGAAGAGCAAGACGGCCACGACCUGGGAGCAGCAGGUCCCAGGUCGCUGGCCGGCUCUGCACCUGUCGCCAUCCCCGGCUCCCUGCCCAGAGCACCAUCGCUACACUCGCCAUCCUCUGCGUCCACCUCGCCGCUCGGUUCGCUGUCCCAGCCCCUCCCAGGGCCGGUGGGCUCCUCAGCCAUGACGCCUCCCCAGCAGCCGCCACCCCUGCGUUCAGAGCCGGGCACACUGGGCUCUGCAGCCUCAUCCUACAGCCCCCUAGGUUUGAACGGUGUCCCCGGGAGCAUCUGGGACUUUGUUUCCGGCAGCUUCUCCCCCAGCCCCUCCCCCAUCCUGAGUGCCGGCCCCCCAUCCUCUUCGAGUGCAAGUCCAAACGGAGCUGAGCUGGCCCGGGUCAGGCGGCAGCUGGACGAGGCCAAGAGGAAGAUCCGGCAGUGGGAGGAGUCCUGGCAGCAGGUGAAGCAGGUCUGCGAUGCCUGGCAGCGAGAGGCGCAGGAGGCCAAGGAGCGUGCCCGUGUGGCCGAUAGCGACCGGCAGCUGGCGCUGCAGAAGAAGGAGGAGGUGGAGGCACAGGUGAAGCAGCUGCAGGAGGAGCUGGAGGGCCUGGGCGUAGCCUCCACACUGCCGGGGCUGCGGGGCUGUGGGGACAUCGGCACCAUUCCCCUGCCGAAGCUGCACUCGCUGCAGAGUCAGCUGCGCCUGGACCUGGAGGCGGUGGACGGCGUGAUCUUCCAGCUCCGCGCCAAGCAGUGUGUGGCCUGCCGGGAGCGGGCCCACGGUGCUGUCCUGCGGCCCUGUCAGCACCACAUCCUCUGUGAGCCGUGUGCGGCCACCGCACCUGAGUGCCCCUACUGCAAGGGCCAGCCCCUGCAGUGGUGACCUCAGCGGGGACAGCCACCUCCUGCUGGGCACCCUGGCUCCAGCGCUCCUCCUGACCACGGACAUGUCGUCACUCGCUUCUGGUGCCACCGACGUGAGGACCGAGGCUGGGAGCCCUUCCUGUUACACGUUAUCAUGAGGCUGGGAGCCCCGCCUGCGCUUGGCCUGACAGCCUUUCCUGUCACACGUUGUCACCUAUCUAGUCCUACCGACGGUUUCAAGGUAUUUUCCUCAAAAACCUUAAAUGCAAACCCACAGAACCCGCCUGCCUGUCCCUGAGGGGCCUGGUGCCUCCGGGAUCCACGCGGCGCUGUGAUCACAGCAGUUUGUGGUCCUGACACUACUGUGACUAGGCCACUGGGAGCUGGGGUCUUUCAAAGCACUUUGUAAACCGAGGAAUUUAGUUAGAGGUUAUAAAUUGCUCUAAGCUGCUUUCUGUUUUUUUUUAAUAUGCGAUAAUAUGAAGCUUUAUAUGUGUACUGUGAACUUAAAUAUUUCAUAUCAGUUUAUUGUCAAUUCAUAGUAUGCUAAAUAUAUUAGAUUUCAUAUUCUGAAACUAGUACUUAUGAAAUGAGUGUUUAUCUAGUAGUAAGACCUAGGAUUUUUACAUUUUCCAAUUAAGUGCAAAUAGUAUUUAUAAGCAGAGUGAUUAUGGAUUGAGAUGUUUUUAACUUGAUGGAAGGAGCUAGUUUUCCUGAGCCUGUGUGUGCACCAGGCACUGGGGCUGAUGUUCCAGCCUCGUGGCGUGGGAGCAGGAGAGCUCCGUCCUGCAUUUCUGUGGUCCGUGGCCGCUGUUUCUGUGCGCCUGCGCCUCGGAGAGCAAGUGAAGGAGCAUCAUGGGUUUUGUUUUCUCCCUUAACCCUCUGAAAGACAGUUUGAUACUAACAAAAAACGCAGCAGAGGGGAUCCGACGUCAGAGCUUUUAGAAUUACUUUUUUAAGCAGCUGUCUUCUGGCUGGGUGCGGUGGCUCAUGCCUGUGAUCCCAGCACUUUGGGAGGCGGGUGGAUCACCUAAGGUCAGGAGUUCAAGACCAGCCUGGCCAACAUGGUGCAACCCCGUCUUAGUAAAAAUACAAAAAUUGGCCUGGCGUGAGAGCGGGCACCUGUAGUCCCAGCUACUCGGGAGGCUGAGGCAGGAGAAUCGCUUGAACCUGGGAGGCAGAGGUUGCAGUGAGCCGAGAUCGCGCCACCGCACUCCAGCCCGGGUGACAGAGCGAGACUCUGGCUCAAAAAAAAAAAAAAAAAGCUGUUUUCUGAUUACUCAGAGCUGUCCUAGGCAAUGGUGCUUUGUAGCUCCUUGGAGAUGUCGCUGGGCGUCCUGGCAGGGGUCAGGCAGUGAACUGGGAGAGUGGUUGCCUCCCCAGCACCCGUGACCACCCUGGUCCUGCUCGUGUGGGAGAUGCUCGGGCCGUGUGUGCGCCAGGGUCCGGGGUGCCGGGUGUAUGUGGCAGUCACCUGACCCGCGCUGCCAGUUAUCAUCGGAGCUCAUCCAUGUGGCCAGUGAGGUCACAGGAGAGGACCCGGCCACAGCCUCUCAGUGGCCUGGAGCACACGGGGGAAGCGACCCCCCCCAGGUCCCGGCUCUGCUGUGGUCCCCUGUCCCGUCUGCCCCUGGAGCGACAGUGUGGUUUCGGCCGCAGCAGAAACGUGACUGAGAACGCAUCCCCGCGAUGACCUGACCCUUCUGCUCAGGGCUGGGACUGUCCCUAGGAGUUGAGCAGGAACAGGCAUCUGUGGUUUACGGCGACCUGGCUCUCCGCGGGCCACGUGGGUGGUGAGGGCACACGAGUGGGAAGCGGCACCGACGUGUUUCUCCCCGACCGUGGCUUUGCCAAAGACUUUUAAUAGCAUUUUUUAAGUGCAAAACGUCUAGGUAAAAAUCUUUAUCAUCAGUGACCAAAUUAGAAUGUAUUUAAUAUAGUAGGUGGUUUAAGAACUGUUUUAACGUAAGACAAACUGAUAGCAACAUUCUGUUGUUUUAAAGGAAGUGGGUCCGUGACAUUCUGCAGCUAGUCCACUACUCCAAGGUAACUAUCGACUUGGUUUCAGUGAAUCUAUUUUGUUUUUAACUACAGUGAUUUAUUAGCUCAGUAUCUAGAAAUUACGUAUAUUUUGUGCUACUGUCAUCGAUGUGUAAACUCUGUUUUUAUUUGUAUUUAUGCACUUGGUUCCCAUUUGGAGCCUCUGGUCUUUUCUGGGAUAAGUGGUGUCUGCCGAGACAUCUCCCGGUUGUCAGUGGUCAGGAGCAGCUGAGCUCUAGUCUGCCAGCUGCUCUGCUCUUUCUGGGAAGGAGGUGGCGCCCGCCCCUCAGGGUGUCUCCAGGGCUCAGCUUCCGGGGUGGUAGAGCUGGGGAGCCCCAGGGGUGGGGGGACAGCUGGGAGAUGGAGGUGGCACCUGCUCCCCUAGAUCAGUACUGGCUCUGAGGACAGGUGAGCAGUGGGAAGACCAAAGAAUGGCUGGCAGCGCUGCCAGGGUUGGAAAUGGGGGCAAGAUCCUGGGGCUGUGUGCCCUGGGGCCUCCCUCACCUGUCUUGGUGGCCAUGGCCUCAGGGAUGGCUCCUAGGUGGCUGAGGCACAGCAGUGGCUGGAAGGUGCCCCGUGGAGGCUGAGGUGGAGGCGCGCCCAGCAGCUCCCCCCUGUGGCCAUGGCGGGCACGGGGCGUAGGAGCUGGCUGGCGGCCGGCUCUGCAUGUUCUUGUUGCCUGUCGUCUGUAACUCUAGUGUUCGACAUUCGCCGUGAUACAGUGGUGUCACGACGUGUGUAACUGUGGUCAGCAGACCUUGUUCCGCGUGGACGCCUCAAGUGGAUUAAUUUCUGGAAGCCUCAAUCUGUAUGUUUGAGUAUUUACAUGAGAAUGUUAUUUGAAUGGAAUUUUCUUAACCCAGAAGGUAGUAUUUAUAAUCAUUUACUUGUAGCGAACUGUUUAAAGUUAACACUUGUUUAAAUUUUUUUACACUAUAGCAUUUAUGCAAUGGUUUACAGAAUUCAUGGAGUUAUUUUUAUCAGUAUGGGAAUUAAUUAAAACCUUGAAUCUUU